GCGGCCCGCAGCGGCGGCGGCAGCGGCGGCGGCGGCUACAGCAGCUCCGCCGGCAGCCGCGGGAGCACGGCGACGCCAGCGGCGGGAAGGGAAAAGGCCGAGGCAUCAGCGUGUGAAGACCGCAAAGACGAUCCCGAGUACAGUUGUGAACAGCAUUGCUGCUAGGCUCCUCCUGCAGAUCAUCUGAAAUGAACCUCUCUUAUUGAUUUUUAUUGGCCUAGAGCCAGGAGUACUGCAUUCAGUUGACUUUCAGGGUAAAAAGAAAACAGUCCUGGUUGUUGUCAUCAUAAACAUAUGGACCAGUGUGAUGGUGAAAUGAGAUGAGGCUCCGCAAUGGAACUGUAGCCACUGCUUUAGCAUUUAUCACUUCCUUCCUUACUUUGUCUUGGUAUACUACAUGGCAAAAUGGGAAAGAAAAACUGAUUGCUUAUCAACGAGAAUUCCUUGCUUUGAAAGAACGUCUUCGAAUAGCUGAACACAGAAUCUCACAGCGCUCUUCUGAAUUAAAUACGAUUGUGCAACAGUUCAAGCGUGUAGGAGCAGAAACAAAUGGAAGUAAGGAUGCGUUGAAUAAGUUUUCAGAUAAUACCCUAAAGCUGUUAAAGGAGUUAACAAGCAAAAAAUCUCUUCAAGUGCCAAGUAUUUAUUAUCAUUUGCCUCAUUUAUUGAAAAAUGAAGGAAGUCUUCAACCUGCUGUACAGAUUGGCAACGGAAGAACAGGAGUUUCAAUAGUCAUGGGCAUUCCCACAGUGAAGAGAGAAGUUAAAUCUUACCUCAUAGAAACUCUUCAUUCCCUUAUUGAUAACCUGUAUCCUGAAGAGAAGUUGGACUGUGUUAUAGUAGUCUUCAUAGGAGAGACAGAUAUUGAUUAUGUACAUGGUGUUGUAGCCAACCUGGAGAAAGAAUUUUCUAAAGAAAUCAGUUCUGGCUUGGUGGAAGUCAUAUCACCCCCUGAAAGCUAUUAUCCUGACUUGACAAACCUAAAGGAGACAUUUGGAGACUCCAAAGAAAGAGUAAGAUGGAGAACAAAGCAAAACCUAGAUUACUGUUUUCUAAUGAUGUAUGCUCAAGAAAAGGGCAUAUAUUACAUUCAGCUUGAAGAUGAUAUUAUUGUCAAACAAAAUUAUUUUAAUACCAUAAAAAAUUUUGCACUUCAACUUUCUUCUGAGGAAUGGAUGAUUCUAGAGUUUUCCCAGCUGGGCUUCAUUGGUAAAAUGUUUCAAGCGCCGGAUCUUACUCUGAUUGUAGAAUUCAUAUUCAUGUUUUACAAGGAGAAACCCAUUGAUUGGCUCCUGGACCAUAUUCUCUGGGUGAAAGUCUGCAACCCUGAAAAAGAUGCAAAACAUUGUGAUAGACAGAAAGCAAAUCUGCGAAUUCGCUUCAGACCUUCCCUUUUCCAACAUGUUGGUCUGCACUCAUCACUAUCAGGAAAAAUCCAAAAACUCACGGAUAAAGAUUAUAUGAAACCAUUACUUCUUAAAAUCCAUGUAAACCCACCUGCGGAGGUAUCUACUUCCUUGAAGGUCUACCAAGGGCAUACGCUGGAGAAAACUUACAUGGGAGAGGAUUUCUUCUGGGCUAUCACACCGAUAGCUGGAGACUACAUCUUGUUUAAAUUUGAUAAACCAGUCAAUGUAGAAAGUUAUUUGUUCCAUAGCGGCAACCAAGAACAUCCUGGAGAUAUUCUGCUAAACACAACUGUGGAAGUUUUGCCUUUUAAGAGUGAAGGUUUGGAAAUAAGCAAAGAAACCAAAGACAAACGAUUAGAAGAUGGCUAUUUCAGAAUAGGAAAAUUUGAGAAUGGUGUUGCAGAAGGAAUGGUGGAUCCAAGUCUCAAUCCCAUUUCAGCCUUUCGACUUUCAGUUAUUCAGAAUUCUGCUGUUUGGGCCAUUCUUAAUGAGAUUCAUAUUAAAAAAGCCACCAACUGAUCAUCUGAGAAACCAACACAUUUUUUCCUGUGAAUUUGUUAAUUAAAGAUAGUUAAGCAUGUAUCUUUUUUUUAUUUCUACUUGAACACUACCUCUUGUGAAGUCUACUGUAGAUAAGACGAUUGUCAUUUCCACUUGGAAAGUGAAUCUCCCAUAAUAAUUGUAUUUGUUUGAAACUAAGCUGUCCUCAGAUUUUAACUUGACUCAAACAUUUUUCAAUUAUGACAGCCUGUUAAUAUGACUUGUACUAUUUUGGUAUUAUACUAAUACAUAAGAGUUGUACAUAUUGUUACAUUCUUUAAAUUUGAGAAAAACUAAUGUUACAUACAUUUUAUGAAGGGGGUACUUUUGAGGUUCACUUAUUUUACUAUUAUAGACCCUCUUUUAUAGAUUAUCAGGGAUUAUAUAUAUAAAUAUAUAAAUAUACAUAAAAAUGUUAUGGAAUUAAUUUAUUAGAAACACUUAAGAAGUACAUAUUUUUGUGCAGUAGAUUUUUGAAUCGAUACUUUUUUUGAAAACCAGUUUCCUUGCUUUUUUAAGUUCUUUCUAUAUUUUUCUUUGGAAAUGCAAACAUUACAAACCAAUGCCAUUUUUCAAAUGCACUGCCAUUUAAGAUUGAUUAUAGAUGGAUUUCUUAAUUGAAGUACUUUUAUAAUCACAGUGACUGAACAAAAUAUUUUCAAAGACAUUUGUCAUUCCUUAAAGCCAAGAUUUUAAAGACUAAUGUCCUUCCUGAGGGUUACUUUACUAUACUGUGUAUGGUGUAUAGCCACAGAAAGUCAGUCUGAUAAAUUUUCAAUGUGUAAGUGUGAUGCAUUCAACCCAGAUUAUUGUAGACUUAACUUAUUAUAUUUCCUCUGAUAUGUAAAAUGACAAACUCUUCUUUCCUUUUUAAUCUUUGUCUUUAAUCCAUGAAUUAGGUGCAUUAUCUGCUGUUGAUUCUUUUAUAUCUGCACUCAUUUUAUGACGUCAGACAAAAUGUUUUCUAGGUGUUGCUAUUGUAUGAGUCAUAAUUGGUAUAAUUUUAAAGAAAAUUGUAAUAUUGUUUUUUGGUGAAAUAUAUUAUUAGUAGUAUAUUUUCCAAAAUGAUUUUAUUGUAGUAUGAACUGAUAAGUGAGUCCCGUGUCCAAGAGACUGUAUUUAUUACUCUUAAACACGCUAUUCCAAAUGAUAUUACUACUAUAAACAAAGAAUAUUACCGGUCUCAGCAAUCAGUGAUCUUUAUAAAAGUACUUUUAAAAAAUGAUGAAUUAUCACCAGGCGCUGUGGCUCACGCCUGUAAUCCCAGCACUUUGGGAGGCCGAGGCGGGCGGAUCACGAGGUCAGGAGAUCAAGACCAUCCUGGCUAACACGGUGAAACCCUGUCUCUACUAAAAAUACAAAAAAUUAGCCAGGCGUGGUGGCAGGUGCCUGUAAUCCCAGCUACUUGGGAGGCUGAGGCAGGAGAAUGGCGUGAACCCAGGAGGCAGAGCUGGCAGUGAGCUGAGAUCGCACCACUGCACUCCAGCCUGGGCGACACAGCUAGACUCCGUCUCAAAAAAAAAAAAAGAUGAAGUAUCAACAUCAGUUCCCAGCCAGUCUGCUUGGACACACUGGGGUGCCACAAGUGGGUUGCAGGUUGGUUGCAGACGGGCAGAGAUGGAUUCUGCUGAGCUUUCAGAGUGACCACUGGCUGGGGCCUAGCGCUGGGGCAAGGUUCCAGCUGGCUGCCUCUAGCCUGGAGGAGCUUCAUCUAGUUACCCAAUGUGCUGAACCAACAGCAUGAAAUAGCAUCAUUUCCUGUGCUGUGUUACAAAGUGCAAACGUUUGGAAACACUGAUACAGUACAAUUAUUUCCAUCACUCCAUGUUGUUAUAAUUUUUAGUUACUUUUCUUGAUUGAAAAGUCAAUCACAUUGCCAAAAAUGAUUUUUAUGUCAGUUAAAGGCCAGUUGAAAUUUUUUUAUUAGGAUGUUUUAAAUUUACUUUUCACUUUCUUGAAUUUUUUUCUUCUCAAAUUUCCUUGGCCCAGUGCCCAUGAGCAAAUUUCAUUCAAAAACAGGAAUAACCUUUUGUCAUAAAAUUUUGGCACCAGCUUGGUAUACUAAAUUACUGCAAAGAUAACUGAGUACCAGAAGUAAAAAUCUCUGCAGGUGGGCUUAGGAGUACUCUUGGGUCCCUGGUUCCUCAGUUGCCAACUCUGGUUUCAUGAAGAAAGACCAUGCUCUGAAAAUCUAGGGAGGAGAAAGUUAUUGCAGCACCUGGUGUGAUUUGUUACAACUUCUUUAAAGACAGCCUGCCUGGCUAGCUUUUUCCUGUUUUCAUGCAGUUUGCCCUCCCAGCAUUGGUCCACCUGUUGUUCCCAAGAAACUCAUUCUUGUUCCCAAGACUCCUUUUAGCCAAAUCUUUCCUAUCAUUCCAGGACUUUUUUGUGCUUCUCUCCCCAUGAAUCUACCCGUGCCUAGGGUGUGUGCCAGGCACGUGGCAGGUGGCCAGUCAGCAUCUGGAUGUGAGACCAAUUAUUCCAGCCUGCCCUCCUCUUUCUCUUUUUAUCAUUUUGUAUUAUUUUUGAGACAGGGUCUCGCUUUGUUGCCCAGGCUGGAGUGCAGUGGUGCUCUCAUAGCUCACUGCAGCCUCGAUCUCUGGCCUCAAGCAAUCCUCCUGCCUCAGCCUCCCAAAGUGCUGGGAUUAUAGGUGUGUGCCACCAUGUCCAGCCCCCUUUCUCUCUCUUAACUCCCUCUCCCUGCUGUCGUUGCCAUACUCUUGCAUACACAAUCGGUUGUCUAGUUUUUGAUUGUUUGUGUGUAUGGUGUGUGCUGUCUCUCUGACCAGAUUUCAGGUUCCUGAGGCGAGCCUGCAGCUCAUACUGCUCAUCUGUCCUCUCCUAUGGUGGGUGCUCAGGGCCUCUCACUGUUAGUUACUCCCUCCUUUCUGCCCAGUUCUGCACUCAACUAGUAGAAGCAGCCAUCCUUUCCCCAAGCAGGAAAUUGUAGUGGUCGCCCUUAAGAGCAGUGUGAGGGCAGAAGAUUAAGGGAGGGGAAGAGUCCCUGGAACUGGAAGAAGGUAAAUACUUUGCCUUGAGAGGGCGCCGAAUCAUUUUACCAAAAUAGUAAAUGGAAAAAGUGUCAAAGGUUGGGACUAGUUUUAAAAACACAUAUAGCCAGUAGACACAUGGGGGCUGUUUAAAUAAAAACAUUUUUUUACCCGGUUCUGCCAUCACACACACUAGUGACAUUCCAAGUACUCAGUGGCCAUGUGGAGCUAGUGGCCACCACACUUGACACCACGGAUGCAGAACUUUUCCAUCACUGCAGAAAGCUCUGUUGAACAGUACUGUGUCCAGAGUGCUAAUUAUGAACAGCUUAGAAACCACAAUUAAUACAUUCUCAUGAGGUUAAAAGCAGACAUGGGAAUAGAACAUAAUGCAAAUGAUGAUGAAUAUUUUGGGUGAGAAGAGAAAGCUGAGGACCCAUUUCUAGGAUUCUAAGAUGUAAGAUUUCUUAAGUUCUUUAUCUUAGUCUCAUGCAUUCUCCACAUCACGCGCUGUACCAUACUGUGUAGUCAGAACAGACAGUGUGAUUGAAAAGCUUUGGAAAAAGUUAACACAAAGGAUUAUUUAGCACAUAGGCUGUAGAUACGUAUGUGUGUAUUUGUUCAACAAUUGGAGAUGGUUGAAUACCCUUGAACAAAGUGUGUAUCUUCUCAAAUCAGUGGUUGCACUAGUCAAUAAUUAGAAGGUGUUGUUAUUUUUAAAACUAUAAGCAAAAUUAUGAAGGCCUUUAAAAAAUCUAUCAUAAUAAUGAAAAAGAGGUUGUCUCCCAACAGUGCUGUCCCUCAAAGAAAAGACUGGUUAUGUGGAAACAGCACGUUUGGAGAGAUUAUUCUAGUGAAUAACAGUGUAUAUUUGUGGUAGGCAAAUUUCUAAGAAUGACCCCUACUGACACCCCCACCAAUGACCUUGUAUAAUAUCCUCCCACUUUGAGCAUGGGUGGAACCUGUUUGAUCCAUGAUUAUAUCAUGUUAUGUAGCAAAAGGAAGACUGUCUGGGGGUGGCUAAUCAAAUCUUGUGACUCCUUUAAAAGCAGAGAGUUUUCUCGGGCUGGUGGCAGAAGUCAAGAGACAAAGCAGAAGGACCUCAGGCACCAUUGCUGUUUUAAGGUAGAGGGGGCUGCAUGAGAAGGAAUGCACAUGGCUUUGAGGAGCUGAGAGAGGCCUUGGCUAACAGCAAAGGAGCUGGGAACUGCAGUCCUACAGCCACGGGAACUGAAUUCAGCCCAUAAGCUCAUUCAUAGGCUUGGAAAGGCAUUCAUCUCCAGUCUCCAGAUAAGACCCAGCCUGGCCAACACUUUGAAUCCAGCCUUGUGAGACCCUAAGCCGAGAACUCACUUAAGCCUGCUUGGACUUCUGACCUACAGAACUAUGAGAUAAUAAAUCAGUGGUGUUUUAAGCUGCUAAAUUUGUGGCAAUUUGUUAUGUAGGAAUAGGAAAUGAAUACAGUAUUUUAAAAGAGGUAAAGAGGAAAUCUUCAUACUUGAUUCCCUGUAGUAUGCUGGAUAUUUCUUGGUAAAUGCAUGAAUAAAGUCUUUAGUAGCAAGUCAUGUACCUGGACCUUGUUGGGGAUGUUCUCGCCAGAGAUCUCAAUUAGUCUUCAUUGGACGUUUGUUGGCAAAGUUGCAGCAUCUUACUGAGUAGCGUUUGGUAAAGGAACUGCUAGAAUGAGACUAUAGGAAUAGGACUGAAACAGUGUGUAAGGGAUCUUUUUUAUUUCUAGAAGAGGUGUUACUUUAUACUGAUUUAGACUGCUCUGAGCCUGUCAGAAGUAAAUUCAAGAAUGAUUAACAGUGGUAUUUUAGAUACAUUAAGAGCAAAAAUAACCUUUGCCUUGUAGAGAUCAGAUAAUCUGUGUAUCGAGGGAUUUAAUUUUUUUUAACCAAAACUUAGUUUCUCUUUUUAUCAUCUAGCACAGAUCAAAUCCUGUAUGGGCCAGCCAAAUGUUUGUAGUUUGAGAAUGUUUUGCAAAUACCUCUCUGCUUCCAAGCCAUUAAUAGCUAAUGAAGUUUUAUUUUGGUUUGUCCAUUAAUUUUUCUGCUUAUUUUUACUGUAUUGCCAUGUCCUUGAUACGAGACAAGUAGAACUAAAAGAGAGAAAAUGAGAGGUUAAGACUGUCAGAAGAUGAGAAAUGUGAGUCAUAACCAUACCUUAGUGUUUUAAGGGAACUUUAUCCAGUCCAAUCCCUUUAUAGAAAAGGAACUUUUCCAAGUUAUGUUGCAGUAUUUAUAGUGUGUAAAAUUUUGUUUGACUUUGGUAGUUGUGCAUUUUAAAUUAUGAAUCUUAUAUGCUACGAUAACUAGUAUGCUUACUUUCUUUAAUGCAUGUGAUCAUACAAUGCUAAAAAGGUAUUUUUUAAAGACCCAACCAAACUGAGGAUUUUGUUAUACAUAUCUGUAUCAACACCUAUAUAUAAACUCUUCUUCUUACCUGAAACACUCCUUCACCCGGUUUGGGCACUAACUAGAUCAUUUUCAAAGGAACAAACAGGAAGGAGCAAGCUGGCACUCCAGGGUGCAUCUGAGCUGAGAAUUUAGAAGACCUCAUUCAAGAAAGUAAACUGAGCAUUGAUGGGAAAGCACUUUGCGCGAAGUAACAUUCCCACUGUUAAUGUUGCAGUCAAAAUUGUGGAAAAAAAAAAGUGGUGCUAAAAUUGUUCUGAAAUGAAGAUUGUUUGUUGUGGGGAAUAUUUUAAUACUCUUGGACUUUAGGGAGGCUAUUUUAUGUGUCACUUGCUCCUAGUUGUUUCAUUGUAUUAGUAAUUAGCAAACUGUCCUGGAACCAAGGGUUUGGUACUUUUGCCUGAUUAGCAUUCCAUUAUUUAUUUGAAAUGCUCAGUGUUUGCUCAAAUUUGGUGAAAAUAUCUUUUGAAGACAUAUUCUCUGAGCCUUAAAAAUGGCUGCUAUCGACAGUACUGUAAGAUGCACUGCCAGUAGAUUUGAUACUUUUCAUUUCAGUGUAGGCAGUAAUGUUUUCUAAGAAAGAUUUAGAAAUCAGCAAAGUGUAACAAUUGUGUUUCAUUUAUGGAAUGGAAAAACUGAAGUGUCCCAUUCAGAACACUUUGGAAAGGUUGUCUGCAUUAGGGGAUGUUUCUGGAAGCAUCCCUUAGAGAAGCUGCCUGAGGAAUCUCCUUGCCAGGUUGUACCAGAUUUUUUUUUUUCUUAAAUGUAUUGUAUAUAUUUUCCUUAAAAUGUCUUCAUUGGCUGAAUGAUUCCUAUCCGUAGUAAUAUUUUAGGUACUUGUUGGAUUUUUAAAGGAAGAUUAUUUAUUUUCAGAUUUGCUGCUAUAAUUGAAAACCUAGUAACUGGUCCUGUUGAUUGUGCCUUCAUCACUGUUUCUCUGUGCCACGACCGUUCAUGUGUAUUUGAAAUAAAGAAGUUUAAAAAGCCAUGUUGAAUUCAAGAUUCCUUCUAAUAAAAAUAGGUGAAACUUAA